CUUUCGGAGGGUGGUGAGCUAGUAAGUGUGGUUUUAGCUGUAGUAGCCAGAUUGGGCGGCCGGGAGUGGUGGGGGUGCCGGGUGGAAGGCUCUGGGCGGGGUCUCAGGACCCUCCUUUUCUUGGCGGGGAUCGGGCUUGUGGUGCCGCUCCCCGUAAUGUACGGAGGAAGAGGGAAAGGGCUCUGGCCCCCUCGGCGUCAUGUCUUCGGUGCUGGCGGCUUCCCAUCCGCUGGUUCUAUCCUCAAACGCCGGGACACCGGGAAUCUCGGAGAAGGACAACCGAGAUCCAGCUGGCUCCUCCAUCGGGGUGCUCACACUUUCUCAUUUGAUUUCAGGUCUGCGGACGCUGUAUACCCUCCUCCACUUCCCGCUGCAGCCAAUAAAGGCCGUUCCUACCAUAGUCUGUGUCCGCGUUCUUUUUUCCGGGACUGCAGAGUUCGGGGAAGCUGUACGCCGCCUUUCGCUACGCGGAAUUUGCAGAUCUUCCCCUGGACCUCAGGCCUCUCCGGCUGGAGUAGGGUGGACGCUUCACAUAAGCUUCUCUGGUCGAACUUACCCGAAUCUCCAGAUGGCCGCGCUGCGUCGAAUGCUCCACUUGCCGAGCCUGAUGAUGGGGACGUGCCGCCCCUUUGCGGGCUCACUGGCUGAUAGUUGCCUGGCGGACCGCUGUCUCUGGGAUCGGCUGCAUGCCCAGCCUCGUUUGGGCACUGUCCCCACCUUCGACUGGUUCUUUGGAUACGACGAAGUCCAGGGGCUCCUACUGCCAUUGCUGCAGGAGGCACAGGCUGCCAGUCCUCUGCGAGUGCUGGAUGUGGGCUGUGGGACUUCCAGCCUAUGUACAGGCCUCUACACCAAAUCUCCACACCCAGUGGAUGUGCUGGGGGUGGACUUUUCUCCUGUGGCUGUGGCCCACAUGAAUAGCCUCCUGGAGGGUGGCCCAGGCCAAACACCUCUAUGCCCUGGACACCCUGCCUCAAGCCUCCACUUCAUGCACGCCGAUGCUCAGAACCUGGGGGCUGUGGCUUCUUCAGGCUCUUUCCAACUACUGCUGGACAAAGGCACAUGGGAUGCUGUUGCCCGGGGAGGUCUGCCUAGGGCUUACCAGCUUCUAUCAGAAUGCUUGAGGGUUCUAAACCCUCAGGGGACCCUGAUUCAGUUCUCAGAUGAGGACCCUGAUGUGCGACUGCCCUGCCUGGAACAAGGGUCCUAUGGCUGGACUGUGACUGUGCAGGAGCUAGGCCCGUUCAGGGGCAUCACCUACUUUGCUUACUUGAUUCAAGGCUCUCAUUAAAGACAUUUUAGUAGUCCUGACCCUAGUAUUUCUGUGGGCAAGGAGAGGGCUGAAGAACUGUCUUUGCAAGCUAUCUGGCUGCAAAGUGAGAAUUUGAGUCCUGGCUUCCACAUUUACUAGCUGGGUGCCAUAUUGCUGAAUGUUUCUGUUCCCCAGUUUACUCAUCUGCAGAGUGAGAAUAACUUGGAGUUACGGAGAUUACAUACAAUGAUGUGCGCAAUAUUUAGCACAAAAUGAAUGCUGAAAAGAGAAGGUACAAUUGGGUCAUUCCCCAGUUUCAACUAACUGGAGCUCCUAAAAGCAGCAGACAGGAACUGAAUCAAAACCCCUGCGCUGACUGACUUGUAUAAUCUAGUGGCCUAACCUGUAAGCCUCAUUUUUGUCACCUGUAAAAGGAGAUUGUAAGAGGAUGGGUAUAAGGAGCUUCAUAAACCUGGAUGAGAUAUUUGAGGGGGAGGGAACAAUACUUACCCUCAAAGCUAUUAGGAGGCAGGAGAUGGGAAUAUUCCACAAAGCCACUUCUACAAACACGGGAGCCUGUUGAGUCCCAGAAGGGACAGUGGUUGGUGGCUUCCAGACAUGCUGUGUCCUCAAGAAUCCAACAAGCAUCUUCUUCAUCCUGGUCCUGCCCCCAGCUGAGUCCAGCGUUAAAUGUUCUUAAAGGACUUCUAGGGUCCUGUGGGCUCCAAGCCCAGCCUGGGAUGGAGGAAGAGAGGGGACAAAAAUAUUACUGAUAUAUUAUCAAAUUACAAAACUAGGCCAGGCAUGCUGGCUCAUACCUAUAAUCACAGCACUUUGGGAGGCCAAGGUGGGCAGAUUGCUUGAGCCCUGGCAAUAAAGUGACACCCCUAACUCUACAAAAACAAAUGAGCCCGGGAUAGUGGCACAGGCAUGUAGUUCCAACUACUCAGGAGGCUGAGCUGGGAGGACUGCUUGAACCCUGGGAGGUCAAAGCUGCAAUGGGCCAUGAUAAGCUGCUGCACUUGAGCUAAAAAUUAAUUUCUGUGGUAUUUUUUGCUUAUAAAAAAAUAGAGCAAUUAUAUCACUAAGAGCCUAA